GUGCUCAGAGAGAGAGAGACUAAGACGGAUAACGCGUCAUCUCGCCUUCCCAAAUUUUCCCCCCUCGCUAGACCGGGUCCAAAACCUCCAUCCGGAGCCGGCAGGAGAGGAGAACGAUGUUUAACUCGGUCAACCUGGGCAACUUCUGCUCUCCGUCGCGCAAGGAGAGGGGCGCAGAUUUCGGCGAGCGAGGGAGCUGCGCCUCCAACCUCUAUCUGCCCAGUUGCACUUACUACAUGCCCGAGUUCUCCACGGUCUCCUCCUUCCUGCCCCAGGCCCCCUCUCGUCAGAUCUCCUAUCCCUACUCGGCCCAAGUGCCCCCGGUCCGGGAGGUCUCCUACGGCCUGGAGCCAUCCGGCAAGUGGCACCAUCGGAACAGCUACUCCUCCUGCUAUGCGGCGGCCGACGAGCUUAUGCACCGGGAGUGCCUGCCUCCUUCCACCGUCACCGAGAUCCUCAUGAAAAACGAAGGCUCCUACGGCGGCCACCACCACCCCAGCGCCCCGCACGCAACCCCCGCCGGCUUCUACUCCUCAGUCAACAAGAACAGCGUCCUGCCUCAAGCCUUCGACCGUUUCUUCGACAACGCCUACUGCGGUGGCGGCGACCCGCCCGCCGAGCCCCCCUGCUCCGGCAAGGGCGAGGCCAAGGGGGAGCCCGAGGCACCCCCGGCCUCGGGACUGGCGUCCCGGGCUGAGGCGGGUGCCGAGGCGGAGGCUGAGGAGGAGAACACAAAUCCCAGCUCGUCCGGUUCAGCCCACUCCGUGGCCAAGGAGCCGGCCAAAGGAGCCGCCCCCAACGCCCCCCGCACCCGCAAGAAGCGCUGCCCUUAUUCGAAAUUCCAGAUCCGGGAACUGGAGCGAGAGUUUUUCUUCAACGUGUAUAUCAACAAAGAGAAGCGGCUGCAGCUGUCCCGGAUGCUGAACCUGACGGACCGACAAGUGAAAAUUUGGUUUCAGAACAGAAGGAUGAAAGAAAAGAAACUGAGCAGAGACCGGCUGCAGUAUUUCUCGGGAAAUCCUCUGCUGUAACCUGCAGACCGGGCCCUUUUGGGGGCGGGGGGAGGGGAAAAUUAUUUUAUUUUAUUUUUAUUUUUUAUUUUCUAACUCGUCUUCUUUCCGCCGGUGGAAAACUGGACUGUGGCCAGGGCUGGCCCCCACCGCUGUGGCCGGCACUCCAUUCCGGAACCUCCUGGACCCUCUAUCUGACUCUCGCUGUGGGACAGGGACCGGGCCUGGAAAGGGGGUGAAGGGAAGUGUCUGAUGCACGGCGAGUGAACACCGUUGGCGCCGAGGCCAAGACUUUGAUUUAAAAGAAAACACACCUCGGCGACAAUGUCUUGCUGCUCGGAUUAGGUGGGGGAGGGGCGACAGUAGUGAGCGCCUGAGCCGAACAAUCCUCGAACUAAAAGCCUUCCCUUGCCCAUGUGAAAAGAUCCGCUAAGACAGCAUGUCUGCCAGCGGAAACUUCUCGAGCUCCCCCCUCUACCCCGCCCCACCUUGCAGCUAAAUGUGAUCCUGCCUUGCUGUGAAAUUUCUGUACCUUCAACCUGGUGUUAGGUGUGCAAAGUCCGUGUCCUACCUCCGUCUUCGCCAAGGCCCCGCCCGAGCCUAGUUGUUCUCCCCCUGAAUGUGUAGAACCUUCCUUUGAAAUUUCUUAAUCGGUGCAUUGAGGUUUCCACAUCUUUUUCCAAGCAGUGCCCCACUUCAUGGAUUUAUAGCUAUAGUCUAUGCAGUCGUUACCUCUUUUUUUUUUUUUUUUAAGAAAAUUGAAGAUUGGGGUGGUGGAGGCAGUAGGGAGAUGGGAUUGGGCACCUCCCCCGUGCUGGGGCCUGGAUUUUUGUAAAUAAAUUUCCCAAGCGUUUCUUUCCACCUGGAGGGAAAGGGGGGGACGCCCCCAGUGAGAUUCAAAUCACGCAUCUCUACUCCUCUGCGUGAGUGCGUGUGUACAUGUGCACUCCCCACCCUGCUCCCUUCCCAGAGGGAUUGCUGUGAAAUUUUUUUGGUGGCAAAUAAAGAUAAAUUUCAUUCUGUUCAAUAUUAUGAUUUUAUUUGACCCUUUUAUUAACCCCUCUCCUCUUAAAAUCCUCCAUGCUCCCAUGGCAGCGGCGGAGGAGGAGGAGGCAGGCAGGCAGAGCCCAGCGGGUGAGGACAGGCAGGCAGAGGUGAGAUAGGCCGGUGCUAGCCGGCCUGGAGCUCCUCUCCGCUGGCAGGGCCAAGAGUAUGGCCGUAGUCUCCUCACAUUCUCAAGCUGAGGACAUUCCAUAGCUACUCUGAAGCUCUCCUUUCUCACGUGCAGCUCGAGCUGUGUCCAAACGCCCAGCAACGGCUUUCUGUUUAAGUACACGUUUGUUGUGGAGUUAAUUGUAACCAUCAUCGAAUUUAAAUUUAUAGGAAUUUUUUUGGCUCCACCGCCCUUCUGCCAGAUGUCUCCGUCUGUCGCAGUUAAAUGUGUAGUGUGGAGGUUAGGGCUUUUUUUUUUUUUUCUCUAGGAGAAAUCUGUAUUGGAAUUUUUAUACACUGUUUUUAAGGAAGGAGGGGACAGAAGGAGAAACCAGCCCCCUCCCUCUCCUCUCCACAGCUCCUGGGGGUGGGAAGGUGGGGCCUGGCUGCUUUCCCUCUGGCACAAAUGGCCAGGCUCUUCCAGACACAACAAGACGCCUAUACUGGGGCCACCCUGAUGUUUAUACAUUGGGUGUCCCACAGUAGAAAGCCCCAGAGGUUUGUUUUGUAGGGGUUGGCACUGGGGAUGGAGAUGACCUGCGGGGACAGUCACCAUACCCAUCUAUAUUUGCUGCAUGUUUCUUCUGUAUAAAGAUAAUCAUGGCCCUUGCAGUGCUUUCAGUGAGGGCACUUCGUUGGUCUCUGUUUCAAAUUCGUUAUUUGGGGGCAGAGGUUCAGGACAACUCAUCUCAUCUUUCCCUCCUCUUUCUGUCUUUGUAUAAUUCAAAGAAAAUAUUUUUGUCAAUACAAUUCUGUUGGAUGAAAGGAAAAAGCAUCAUGACUAUCAAAUCUAGGUUCUGUCAUUUUUGAUGGUAGGAAUCCCUGCAGCUUAGGUAUCUAAAUUUCUAAUUUGUAAACGUGGGUCGGGUCGUGAGACAAGAUUUGCAAACUAGGGUGUAUAUGCAGCCCACAAUUCCCUCAUGUGCCCACACACAAACGUUUUAUUUAACUCGGUGUGCCUAUGGGUGCACAUAAGAAGGAAUAUUAUUUAUAUGCUUUUGUCUGUUGCAUGGAGUAAACCUGACCACAUACACAUCUA